CCUUUGUCUCUCGCUGCAGCCGGAGGUCAAGGUCUCGUCCUUACUGCUGUGUGUCCUCUGCUCCUAGAGUCCCAGCCUCUGUGGCCCUAUGACCUGCAGGUAUUGGGAGAUCCACAACUAAGUCGCCAGGACCCCCUGGAAGCCUAGAAAUGGGAUCAUUGACAUUUAGGGAUGUGGCCAUAGAAUUCUCUCUGGAGGAGUGGCAAUGCCUGGACACUGCACAGCAGAAUUUAUAUAGAAAUGUGAUGUUAGAGAACUACAGAAACCUGGUCUUCCUGGGUAUUGCUGCCUUUAAGCCAGACCUGAUCAUUUUUCUGGAGGAAGGAAAAGAGUCCUGGAAUAUGAAGAGACAUGAGAUGGUGGAAGAAUCCCCAGUUAUAUGUUCUCAUUUUGCUCAAGAUCUUUGGCCAGAGCAGGGCAUAGAAGAUUCUUUCCAAAAAGUGAUAUUGAGAAGGUAUGAAAAAUGUGGACAUGAGAAUUUACACUUAAAAAUUGGUUAUACCAAUGUGGAUGAGUGUAAGGUGCACAAAGAAGGUUAUAAUAAACUUAACCAGAGUUUGACAACUACACAGAGCAAAGUAUUUCAACGUGGCAAAUAUGCAAAUGUCUUUCAUAAAUGUUCAAAUUCAAACAGACAUAAGAUAAGGCAUACUGGAAAGAAACAUUUGCAAUGUAAAGAAUACGUCAGAUCAUUUUGCAUGCUUUCACACCUAUCUCAACAUAAAAGAAUUUAUACUAGAGAGAAUUCCUACAAAUGUGAAGAAGGUGGCAAAGCUUUUAACUGGUCCUCAACCCUUACUUAUUAUAAGAGUGCUCAUACUGGAGAGAAACCCUACAGAUGUAAAGAAUGUGGCAAAGCCUUUAGUAAGUUCUCAAUCCUUACUAAACAUAAGGUAAUUCAUACUGGAGAGAAAUCCUACAAAUGUGAAGAAUGUGGCAAGGCUUUUAACCAAUCUGCAAUCCUUACUAAACAUAAGAUAAUUCAUACUGGAGAGAAACCCAACAAAUGUGAAGAAUGUGGCAAAGCCUUUAGUAAGGUCUCGACUCUUACUACACAUAAGGCAAUUCAUGCUGGAGAGAAGCCCUACAAAUGUAAAGAAUGUGGCAAAGCCUUCAGUAAGGUCUCAACCCUUAUUACACAUAAGGCAAUUCAUGCUGGAGAGAAGCCCUACAAAUGUAAAGAAUGUGGCAAAGCCUUUAGUAAGUUCUCAAUCCUUACUAAACAUAAGGUAAUUCAUACUGGAGAGAAACCCUACAAAUGUGAAGAAUGCGGCAAAGCCUAUAAGUGGCCCUCAACCCUUAGUUAUCAUAAGAAAAUUCAUACUGGAGAGAAACCCUACAAAUGUGAAGAAUGUGGCAAAGGUUUUAGUAUGUUCUCAAUCCUUACUAAACAUGAGGUCAUUCAUACUGGAGAGAAACCCUACAAAUGUGAAGAAUGUGGCAAAGCUUUCAACUGGUCCUCAAACCUUAUGGAACAUAAGAAAAUUCACACUGGAGAGACACCCUACAAAUGUGAAGAAUGUGGCAAAGGCUUUAGUAUGUUCUCAAUCCUUACUAAACAUAAGGUAAUUCAUAAUGGAGAGAAACCCUACAAAUGUGAAGAAUGUGAUAAGGCAACUCAUGCUGGAGAGAAACCCUACAAAUGUGAAGAAUGUGGCAAAGCUUUCAACUGGUCCUCAAACCUUAUGGAACAUAAGAGAAUUCAUACUGGAGAGAAACCCUACAAAUGUGAAGAAUGUGGCAAAAGCUUCAGUACAUUCUCAAUCCUUACUAAACAUAAGGUAAUUCAUACUGGAGAGAAACCCUACAAAUGUGAAGAAUGUGGCAAAGCCUAUAAGUGGUCCUCAACCCUUAGUUAUCAUAAGAAAAUUCAUACUGUAGAGAAACCCUACAAAUGUGAAGAAUGUGGCAAAGCUUUUAACCAAUCUGCAAUUCUUAUUAAACAUAAGAGAAUUCAUACUGGUGAGAAACCCUACAAAUGUGAAGAAUGUGGCAAAACCUUUAGUAAGGUCUCAACCCUUACUACACAUAAGGCAAUUCAUGCUGGAGAGAAGCCCUACAAAUGUAAAGAAUGUGGCAAAACCUUUAUUAAGGUCUCAACCCUUACUACACAUAAGGCAAUUCAUGCUGGAGAGAAGCCCUACAAAUGUAAAGAAUGUGGCAAAGCCUUUAGUAAGUUCUCAAUCCUUACUAAACAUAAGGUAAUUCAUACUGGAGAGAAACCCUACAAAUGUGAAGAAUGUGGCAAAGCUUUCAACUGGUCCUCAAACCUUAUGGAACAUAAGAGAAUUCAUACUGGAGAGAAACCCUACAAAUGUGAAGAAUGUGGCAAAAGCUUUAGUACAUUCUCAGUCCUUACUAAACAUAAGGUAAUUCAUACUGGAGAGAAACCCUACAAAUGUGAAGAAUGUGGCAAAGCCUAUAAGUGGUCCUCAACCCUUAGUUAUCAUAAGAAAAUUCAUACUGUAGAGAAACCCUACAAAUGUGAAGAAUGUGGCAAAGCUUUUAACCGAUCUGCAAUCCUUAUUAAACAUAAGAGAAUUCAUACUGAUGAGAAACCCUACAAAUGUGAAGAAUGUGGCAAAACCUUUAGUAAGGUCUCAACCCUUACUACACAUAAGGCAAUUCAUGCUGGAGAAAAGCCCUACAAAUGUAAAGAAUGUGGCAAAGCCUUUAGUAAGUUCUCAAUCCUUACUAAACAUAAGGUAAUUCAUACUGGAGAGAAACCCUACAAAUGUGAAGAAUGUGGCAAAGCCUAUAAAUGGCCCUCAACCCUUAGUUAUCAUAAGAAAAUUCAUACUGGAGAGAAACCCUACAAAUGUGAAGAAUGUGGCAAAGGUUUUAGUAUGUUCUCCAUCCUUACUAAACAUGAGGUAAUUCAUACUGGAGAGAAACCCUACAAAUGUGAAGAAUGUGGCAAAGCCUUCAGCUGGUUGUCAGUCUUUAGUAAACAUAAGAAAACUCAUGCUGGAGAGAAAUUCUACAAAUGUGAAGCAUGUGGCAAAGCCUAUAAGUCAUCCUCAACCCUUAGUUAUCAUAAGAAAAUUCAUACUGAAGAGAAACCUUACAAAUAUGAAGAAUGUGGCAAAGGCUUUAGUACAUUCUCAAUCCUUACUAAACAUAAGGUAAUUCAUACUGGAGAGAAACCCUACAAAUGUGAAGAAUGUGGCAAAGCUUUCAACUGGUCAUCAAACCUUAUGGAACAUAAGAAAAUUCACACUGGAGAGACACCCUACAAAUGUGAAGAAUGUGACAAAGCCUUCAGCUGGCCCUCAAGCCUUACUGAACAUAAGGCAACUCAUGCUGGAGAAAAACCCUACAAAUGUGAAGAAUGUGGCAAAGCCUUCAGCUGGCCCUCAAGACUUACUGAACAUAAGGCAACUCAUGCUGGAGAGGAACCCUACAAAUGUGAAGAAUGUGGCAAAGCUUUCAACUGGUCCUCAAACCUUAUGGAACAUAAGAGAAUUCAUACUGGAGAGAAACCCUACAAAUGUGAAGAAUGUGGCAAAAGCUUUAGUACGUUCUCAAUCCUUACUAAACAUAAGGUAAUUCAUACUGGAGAGAAACCCUACAAAUGUGAAGAAUGUGGCAAAGCCUAUAAGUGGUCCUCAACCCUUAGUUAUCAUAAGAAAAUUCAUACUGUAGAGAAACCCUACAAAUGUGAAGAAUGUGGCAAAGGCUUUGUUAUGUUCUCAAUCCUUGCAAAACAUAAGGUAAUUCAUACUGGAGAGAAACUCUACAAAUGUGAAGAAUGUGGCAAAGCCUAUAAGUGGCCCUCAACCCUUAGAUAUCACAAGAAAAUUCAUACUGGAGAGAAACCCUACAAAUGUGAAGAAUGUGGCAAAGCCUUUAGUACGUUCUCAAUCCUCACUAAACAUAAGGUAAUUCAUACUGGAGAGAAACCCUACAAAUGUGAAGAAUGUGGCAAAGCCUUCAGCUGGUUAUCAGUCUUCAGUAAACAUAAGAAAAUUCAUACUGGAGAGAAACUCUAGAAAUGUGAAGAAUGUGGCAAAGCCUAUAAGUGGCCCUCAACCCUUAGUUAUCAUAAGAAAAUUCAUACUGGAGAGAAACCCUACAAAUGUGAAGAAUGUGGUGAGGCUUUCAACUGGUCCUCAAACCUUAUGGAACAUAAGAGAAUUCAUACUGGAGAGACACCCUACAAAUGUGAAGAAUGUGGUAAAGGCUUUAGUAUGUUCUCAAUCCUUACUAAACAUAAGGUAAUUCAUACUGGAGAGAAACCAUACAAAUGCAAAGAAUGUGGCAAAGCCUAUAAGUGGUCCUCAACCCUCAGUUAUCAUAGAAAAUUCAUACUGGAGAGAAACCCUACAAAUGUGAAGAAAGUGGCAAAGCCUUCAGCUGGUUCUCAGUCUUUAGUAAACAUAAGAAAAUUCAUGCUGGAGAGAAAUUCUAAAAAUGUGAAGAAUUUGGCAAAGCUUUUAAACAGUUCCCAACCCUCCUACACAUAAGAAAAUUCAUGCUGGAGAGAAACUCUACAAAUGAGAAGAAUGUGGCAAAGGCUUCAACCAGUCCUCAAACCUUAUGGAACAUAAGAGAAUUCAUACUGGUGAGAAGCCCUACAAAUGUGAAGAAUGUGAUAAAGACUUCAACUGGUCCUCACACCUUACUACUCAUAAAAGAAUUCAUACUGGAGGAAAAACCCUACAAAUAUGAAAAAUGUGGCAAAACUAUUAAUUAAUUCUCAACGCUUACUGAACAUAAGGGAAUUUGUACAGGAGGGAAACCCUACAAAUCUGAAGAAUGUGGCAAGCCUUUUAGCUAUUCCUCAAUCCUUACUAAACAUUCAUGUAAUUCAUACUGGAGGGAAUUCCUACAAUUGUGUGGAAUGUUGCAAUGCCCUUAACCAGUCCUUAAGGCUUACUACAUAUAAGACAACUCAUACUGGAGAGAAACCAUGCAUGUGUGAAGAAUGUGGGAAAGCCUCUAAUAGAUCCUCAAUUCUUAAGAGACAUAAGCUAAUUCAUACACAAGAGAGACUCUACAAACCUGAAAGAUGUGACAAUGCUUUUGGCAACACCUCAGACUUUUCUGAAUAUAAAAGAAAUCGUACAGAUGAGAAAUCCUAGAAAAGUGAAGAAUAUGACAAAGCCUUUAAGUGGCUGUCACACUUGAUUGUAGGUAAGAUAACUCAUACUGGAGAAAACUACUGUAAUAAACAAUGUGACAAACAUUUAACCAGUGCUCAUGCCUUAUUGCAAAGGAAAGCAUUUACACUAGCCUGGGCAACAGAGAGAGACUGUCUGGAAAAAAAAAUUUUUGUUAAUGCCAGUAAUAUCUUCUCACAGCUUAUUAAACAUCAGAGAGUUCAUACUAAAUAAAAGUAUUAAAAGUGCAAUCACUGUCACUAGAUCUUUCAGAAAAUAAAAGCUGUUAAAGUACAGAAGAAUAUUUAUUUUGAGGAAACACAUUAUAAAUAUUAAGAGGGUUGUAGUACAUGUACUUGUAUCACAGAUUUUAUUGUACACAUUUUGUACUACAGGAAAACCUGAGGUAGUUGUUCCAACUUUGCUCAACAUCAGGGAAUUUAUAUUGAAGAAUAACCCUGCAAAUUUAAUAAAUUUGGAAAAACAUUUUUUCAAAAACUACAGAUUAUAAAACACAAAUGCGUUUAUACUAAAAUAUGUUUUUGCAGAUACAGUAAAUAUAAAAAAUAUUUAAUCCAAAAUUAAGUUUAUGUAAAUAUCAGCUAAUUCACAGUAGAAAUACCUGUCACUCAAACUUCAGAUAUUACACUAAAUCAGACUGCUGAGUAUAGGAAAAAAUCCAAAACUAAAGUUGGCAAAAAGAAGAAUUAUUUGUAUAUAACUUUAAAAGAAGUAGAUCUUUGAAGAGUUAUAAUUAAAUUUAAAGUAUACUUUUUUCUUCAAAACACAGAUUUUUUUUUUUUCCAGACACAUUGGCUUACUGUGGCCAAUACUUUGUGAUGCCAAGGUGGGCAGAUCACCUGAGGUCAGGAGUUCAAGACCAGCCUUGCCAACAUAGUGGAACUAAAAAGAAAUGUUUACUAAACAUGUUUACUAAAAAGAAAUAAAGAAAUUAGCCAAGGUCUAGCUUCCAGGUUCAUGCCAUUCUCCCACCUCAGCCUCCCAAUUAGCUGGGACUACAGGCGCCCGCCGCCACUCCCAGCUAAUUUUUUGUAUUUUUAGUACAGAUGGGGUUUCACCAUAUUAGCCAGGACGGUCUCUAUCUCCUGACCUCAUGAUAUGCCCACCUUGGCCACCCAAAGUCCUGGGAUUGCAGGCAUGAGCCACAGUGCCUGGCCUAAUAACAGAAGUCUUUAGCAGAGCAAAAAUGUAUAAAAUGUAUAAUGACAUUGUAUAAGUAAUAAUAAACCUACUAACCAUAAAAAGCCCUGGAUCAUAUGAAAUCACAGCGAAGUUUUACCACAUUGCAAAGAGUUUUACCUAAGCCUACUGAAUGCAUUCGAAAAAAUCAAGGUGGGAUUUCACCCUAACUUGUUAUAUUAAAUCAGUGAAAUAUAUGAAACUAAAAUCUAGUGAAGGCACCACAAAAAAAGGAAAGUACAGGUCAAUAUUCUGGGUGAAUAUUGGAAUAAUAAUCCUCCAUGAAAUACUAGCAAACUGAAUUCAAAAGCAAAUCAGAAAGUUAUUUUGCUACAUUAAUGUGAGCUUUUCCAUAUAUAUGAAGGUGUUUCAUGAUAUGGAAGUCAAUAAGUGUGAUUCACCAUGUAAAGAUAAUUAAAAGAAAAAAAAAUAACAGUAGGGGCAGAAAAAGCAUUCAAGAAAACCCAAUAUUAACUCAAAAAUGUUGUCAACACACUGGACAUUGAUGAAAAUAUCUUAAUAAGAGUCAUCUAUGACAAAUCCUUAGCCAACAUCAUACUAAAAGAGCAAAAACUGGAAGCAUUCUCCAUGAGAAUAAAAAUAAGAAUAUCCAUUCUAAACAGUCCUAUUGAAGUUAUGAAAUCCUAGCCAGAGAAUAAAAGGAAUCCAAACAGAAAACAAAGAAAGUCAAAUUAUCUUUACUGAUGAAAGAAUUGUCCACCUAGAAUACUUUAAAGGUUUCACCAAAAGAGUUCUAAGCCUGGAAAAAGACUUCAAAAAAAAUCUUAGAAUACAAAAUCAGCACAAAUGCAUAGCAUUUCUGUACACCAAUAAUAUUCAAACUGAGAACAAAAUAAAAAACACAGCUCUAUUUACAAUAGCAACAAACACACAAAAAAAUACCUAGAAAUACAUUAAAUCAAGGGGGUAAAAUAUCUCUACAAAGAACAACAAAACAUUGCUGAAAGAAACGAGAGACAAUGCAAAUAAAUGGAAAAAUAUUGCUCAUGGAUUCAAAUAAUAUAAUUAAAAUGGUCAUUCUGCCUAAAGCAACCUACAGAUUAAGUGCUAUUUUUAUCAGACUAUCCAUGACGAUUUUUAUUGAAUUAGAAAAAGAAAACUAUUCUAAAAUACAUUCAAAAGAAUUAAAGAGCUCAAAUAGCCAAGAAAACUUCAGACUAAAAGAAUAAAUCUGGGCCAAGCAUGGUGGCUCAUGCCUGUCAUCUCAGCCCUUUGGGAGGCUGAGAUGGAUGGAUCACCUGAGGUCAGAAGUUUGAGACCAGCCUGGCCAACAUGGUGAAACCUGCAUCUCUACUAAAUGUAAAAAAUUAGCCAGGUGUGGUGGUGCAUGCCUGUAAUCCCAGCUACUUGGGAGGCUGAGGAAAGAGAACCAUUUGAGCCUGGGAGGUGGAGGUUGCAGUGAGCCAAGAUUGCAUCAGAAUAACCAGUAUAACAUGGUUCUGGUACAAAAAUAAACAUCUAGACCAAUGAAAUGGAAGAGAGAGUACUGAAUUAAGCUAUACUUUGCAAUCAGGUUAUUUUUACAAAGCCAACAGAAAUAAACAAAAGGGGAAUUAACUCCCUAUUUAGUAAGUAAUACUGGGAAAACUGGUUAGUCAUAUGUGGAAGAAAACUGUACUACCUUUUUCUAUAAAAAAAAAACAACUCAAUAUAGAUUAAAGACUUGAUCUGUGAGUCUCCAAGCUACAAAAAUCUUAGAAUAACACUUAGAUAAUACUGGCCUCUGUAAAGAAUUUAUGACUAACAUCUAACAUGAGUGCAACAAAAAUAAAAAUAAAAAAUGGCAUCUAAGCCAAAGAGCUUCUGCACAGUAAAAGAAACUAUCAGCAAAGUAAACAGAUGACCUACAGUAUGAAAUAAAAUAUUUGCAAACUGCAGACAAUGAAGGAUUAAUGUACAGAAUCUAUAAUACAUUUAAUAAAAAAGCAAACAUGAUAUGAAUAGCCAGCUUCUUCUCAAAGGAAGACAUAAGAGCUGCCAAUAAACAUGUAAAAAUUGCUCAACGUUCCUAAUUAUCAGAAAGAUGUAAAUCAAAGUGACAGUGUGAUACUAUUUCAUACCAGUAAGAAUGACUUAUUAAAAGUAAGAUAAAUAAGAUGUUGAAGUUGUAGAGAUAAGGAAAUCUUUCUACACUGUUGGUGGGAAUGCAAAUUAAUUCAGAACCUGUGCAAAGCAGUUUGGGGACUUCUCAAAGAACUAGAAAUAGAAUUGCCAUUUGACCAAUCAAGCCGAUUACUGGAUAUCUGCCCCCAAAAAGAAUAAAUAAUUUUGCCAAAGAGACACCAGCACUCACAUGUUCAUUGCAGCACUAUUCACAAUAGCAAAAACAGAAUUUAACCAGUUACCCAUGAAUCUUUUAUUGGAUAAGAAAAAUGAUGUACUUAUACAACCUCCAAUACUAUGCAGCAACAGAAGAGAAUGAAGUAACGUCUUUUGCAGCAACAUGAAUGCAGCUCUGCUUCAGGCCAUUCUAAGCAAAUUAUUGCAUCAGAAAAACAAAUGCCACAUGUUCUCACUCAUACAUGGAUGCUAAAAAUUGGGCGCACAUGGAAACAAAGAUGAAAACAAUAAACACUGAGAAUUCUAAAAAGAAGGAGGAAGGAUGGGAGACAAGCAUAGAAAAUCUGCUUAGGUAUGAUGUACACUACUUGGGCAAUGGAAUUAUUAAGUAUCCAAACCUCAACAUCAUGUAGUCUACCUGUUUUACAAAUCUGCACAUGUACCUUAAAUAUAAAAUAAAAAUAAUAAAAUGUUUUUUGGUAUAA